ACUGUAUAUACAAUCUGGGUCAGCUGCAGCUGGUUACUGCAUUUCUCCAUGUGGCAGACAGAGCAAAGCCACAACGCUUUCUCUGCUGGAUUAAAGACGGCCCACAGACCAGAACUUCCACUAUACUACUUAAAAUUACAUAGGUGGCUUGUCAAAUUCAAUUGAUUAGUAUUGUAAAAGGAAAAAGAAGUUCCUUCUUACAGCUUGGAUUCAACGGUCCAAAACAAAAAUGCAGCUGCCAUUAAAGUCACAGAUGAACAAACUUCUACACUGAUUUUUAAAAUCAAGAAUAAGGGCAGCAAGUUUCUGGAUUCACUGAAUCAACAGACACAAAAAGCUGGCAAUAUAGCAACUAUGAAGAGAAAAGCUACUAAUAAAAUUAACCCAACGCAUAGAAGACUUUUUUUUCUCUUCUAAAAACAACUAAGUAAAGACUUAAAUUUAAACACAUCAUUUUACAACCUCAUUUCAAAAUGAAGACUUUUACCUGGACCCUAGGUGUGCUAUUCUUCCUACUAGUGGACACUGGACAUUGCAGAGGUGGACAAUUCAAAAUUAAAAAAAUAAACCAGAGAAGAUACCCUCGUGCCACAGAUGGUAAAGAGGAAGCAAAGAAAUGUGCAUACACAUUCCUGGUACCUGAACAAAGAAUAACAGGGCCAAUCUGUGUCAACACCAAGGGGCAAGAUGCAAGUACCAUUAAAGACAUGAUCACCAGGAUGGACCUUGAAAACCUGAAGGAUGUGCUCUCCAGGCAGAAGCGGGAGAUAGAUGUUCUGCAACUGGUGGUGGAUGUAGAUGGAAACAUUGUGAAUGAGGUAAAGCUGCUGAGAAAGGAAAGCCGUAACAUGAACUCUCGUGUUACUCAACUCUAUAUGCAAUUAUUACAUGAGAUUAUCCGUAAGAGGGAUAAUUCACUUGAACUUUCCCAACUGGAAAACAAAAUCCUCAAUGUCACCACAGAAAUGUUGAAGAUGGCAACAAGAUACAGGGAACUAGAGGUGAAAUACGCUUCCUUGACUGAUCUUGUCAAUAACCAAUCUGUGAUGAUCACUUUGUUGGAAGAACAGUGCUUGAGGAUAUUUUCCCGACAAGACACCCAUGUGUCUCCCCCACUUGUCCAGGUGGUGCCACAACAUAUUCCUAACAGCCAACAGUAUACUCCUGGUCUGCUGGGAGGUAACGAGAUUCAGAGGGAUCCAGGUUAUCCCAGAGAUUUAAUGCCACCACCUGAUCUGGCAACUUCUCCCACCAAAAGCCCUUUCAAGAUACCACCGGUAACUUUCAUCAAUGAAGGACCAUUCAAAGACUGUCAGCAAGCAAAAGAAGCUGGGCAUUCGGUCAGUGGGAUUUAUAUGAUUAAACCUGAAAACAGCAAUGGACCAAUGCAGUUAUGGUGUGAAAACAGUUUGGACCCUGGGGGUUGGACUGUUAUUCAGAAAAGAACAGACGGCUCUGUCAACUUCUUCAGAAAUUGGGAAAAUUAUAAGAAAGGGUUUGGAAACAUUGACGGAGAAUACUGGCUUGGACUGGAAAAUAUCUAUAUGCUUAGCAAUCAAGAUAAUUACAAGUUAUUGAUUGAAUUAGAAGACUGGAGUGAUAAAAAAGUCUAUGCAGAAUACAGCAGCUUUCGUCUGGAACCUGAAAGUGAAUUCUAUAGACUGCGCCUGGGAACUUACCAGGGAAAUGCAGGGGAUUCUAUGAUGUGGCAUAAUGGUAAACAAUUCACCACACUGGACAGAGAUAAAGAUAUGUAUGCAGGAAACUGCGCCCACUUUCAUAAAGGAGGCUGGUGGUACAAUGCCUGUGCACAUUCUAACCUAAAUGGAGUAUGGUACAGAGGAGGCCAUUACAGAAGCAAGCACCAAGAUGGAAUUUUCUGGGCCGAAUACAGAGGCGGGUCAUACUCCUUAAGAGCAGUUCAGAUGAUGAUCAAGCCUAUUGACUGAAGAGAGACACUCGCCAAUUUAAAUGACACAGAACUUUGUACUUUUCAGCUCUUAAAAAUGUAAAUGUUACAUGUAUAUUACUUGGCACAAUUUAUUUCUACACAGAAAGUUUUUAAAAUGAAUUUUACCGUAACUAUAAAAGGGAACCUAUAAAUGUAGUUUCAUCUGUCGUCAAUUACUGCAGAAAAUUAUGUGUAUCCACAACCUAGUUAUUUUAAAAAUUAUGUUGACUAAAUACAAAGUUUGUUUUCUAAAAUGUAAAUAUUUGCCACAAUGUAAAGCAAAUCUUAGCUAUAUUUUAAAUCAUAAAUAACAUGUUCAAGAUACUUAACAAUUUAUUUAAAAUCUAAGAUUGCUCUAACGUCUAGUGAAAAAAAUAUUUUUAAAAUUUCAGCCAAAUAAUGCAUUUUAUUUAUAAAAAUACAGACAGAAAAUUAGGGAGAAACCUCUAGUUUUGCCAAUAGAAAAUGCUUCUUCCAUUGAAUAAAAGUUAUUUCAAAUUGAAUUUGUGCCUUUCACACGUAAUGAUUAAAUCUGAAUUCUUAAUAAUAUAUCCUAUGCUGAUUUUCCCAAAACAUGACCCAUAGUAUUAAAUACAUAUCAUUUUUAAAAAUAAAAAAAAACCCAAAAAUAAUGCAUGCAUAAUUUAAAUGGUCAAUUUAUAAAGACAAAUCUAUGAAUGAAUUUUUCAGUGUUAUCUUCAUAUGAUAUGCUGAACACCAAAAUCUCCAGAAAUGCAUUUUAUGUAGUUCUAAAAUCAGCAAAAUAUUGGUAUUACAAAAAUGCAGAAUAUUUAGUGUGCUACAGAUCUGAAUUAUAGUUCUAAUUUAUUAUUACUUUUUUUCUAAUUUACUGAUCUUACUACUACAAAGAAAAAAAAACCCAACCAAUCUGCAAUUCAAAUCAGAAAGUUUGGACAGCUUUACAAGUAUUAGUGCAUGCUCAGAACAGGUGGGACUAAAACAAACUCAAGGAACUGUUGGCUGUUUUCCCGAUACUGAGAAUUCAACAGCUCCAGAGCAGAAGCCACAGGGGCAUAGCUUAGUCCAAACUGCUAAUUUCAUUUUACAGUGUAUGUAACGCUUAGUCUCACAGUGUCUUUAACUCAUCUUUGCAAUCAACAACUUUACUAGUGACUUUCUGGAACAAUUUCCUUUCAGGAAUACAUAUUCACUGCUUAGAGGUGACCUUGCCUUAAUAUAUUUGUGAAGUUAAAAUUUUAAAGAUAGCUCAUGAAACUUUUGCUUAAGCAAAAAGAAAACCUCGAAUUGAAAUGUGUGAGGCAAACUAUGCAUGGGAAUAGCUUAAUGUGAAGAUAAUCAUUUGGACAACUCAAAUCCAUCAACAUGACCAAUGUUUUUCAUCUGCCACAUCUCAAAAUAAAACUUCUGGUGAAACAAAUUAAACAAAAUAUCCAAACCUCAUAGUGGUAUUAUUCUUUGUUUUACCUGUGGUCAUCUUAAACUGGUUUUUCAGUCCCUCUCCACUUCCUUCAGAACCAAAGAAUCUGUUAUAAGAUUCCUGGAAGGAACUGGGCAUCUAACUGUUACACCAAAUCUUAAGUGAAUAAAACUUUACCAAGGCUUCUCAGUUA